AAAUUGGAGGCAGCAGAGCCUGGGAGCAGCCUCCACGGCGGCAGCGGCCGCCCCAGUCCCAGCCCCAGCCCCAGCCCCAGCCCCGCCCCCGCCCCGCGCCCCGCCGGAGACGCCCGGAUCGGCGGAGCCUGGCGCGAGCCCUCGCCCCCUCGCCUCUCCCGCCGCGCCUCCGCCUGCCCGCCCCCGCCGGCCGAGGCUGGGCUGCGGGAGGCGGCCGGGCGGCCCCGAGCUUCGCUAGGGCGACCAAAACAAAGGCAGCAUCCGGGGCUGGGUGGAUGCAAACAACCAUGAAAGACUGGGUUCUCGCUCUCCCCGGCUCUGCUGCUGCUGCUGCUGCCGCCGCCGCCGCUGCUCCUCCUCCUGCCGCCGCCGCUAGGGCUCCGCUGUGAGGGGGAAGCAGGGGCGCAGCUGCUGGGCGUGCAUCCGAAAGGUGAGAGCCAGAGAGCGAGCAGAGGGGGCGGGCAGGCCACGAAAAUGUCCUCGGCCGUGGGGCCCCGCGGUCCUCGCCCACCCACGGUGCCUCCCCCCAUGCAAGAGCUGCCCGACCUGAGCCACCUGACCGAAGAGGAGAGGAACAUUAUCAUGGCAGUGAUGGACCGGCAGAAGGAAGAGGAGGAAAAAGAAGAAGCCAUGCUCAAGUGUGUUGUCAGGGACAUGGCGAAGCCUGCUGCCUGCAAAACACCAAGAAAUGCUGAAAACCAGCCCCACCAACCUUCACCGAGAUUGCAUCAACAGUUUGAAAGCUAUAAGGAACAAGUGAGAAAAAUAGGGGAAGAAGCGCGGCGUUACCAGGGCGAGCACAAAGACGAUGCUCCGACUUGUGGAAUCUGUCAUAAAACAAAGUUUGCUGAUGGGUGCGGUCAUCUCUGCUCCUAUUGUCGCACUAAGUUCUGUGCGCGCUGCGGAGGCCGCGUGUCUCUACGGUCAAACAACGAGGACAAAGUGGUUAUGUGGGUAUGCAAUUUAUGUCGAAAGCAACAAGAAAUCUUAACCAAAUCUGGGGCAUGGUUCUUUGGAAGUGGCCCUCAGCAGACAAGUCAGGAUGGAACCCUGAGUGAUACAGCUACAGGUGCUGGCUCUGAGGUACCAAGAGAAAAGAAAGCACGACUCCAAGAGCGAUCGCGGUCUCAGACACCCCUAAGCACAGCAGCUGCCUCCUCCCAGGAUGCUGCUCCUCCCAGCGCACCACCAGACAGGAGCAAAGGGGCUGAGCCCUCGCAGCAAGCCUUGGGGCCUGAACAGAAGCAGGCUUCAUCCAGGUCUAGAAGUGAACCUCCUAGAGAGAGAAAGAAGACCCCAGGGCUUUCCGAGCAGAAUGGCAAAGGAGCCCUGAAGAGCGAGCGGAAACGCGUGCCAAAGACCUCAGCGCAGCCCGUGGAGGGGGCCGUCGAAGAACGGGAGCGCAAAGAAAGGCGGGAAAGCCGAAGGCUUGAGAAAGGGCGAUCACAGGAUUACCCAGACACGCCGGAAAAACGGGAUGAGGGCAAAGCGGCGGAUGAGGAAAAGCAAAGAAAAGAGGAGGAUUAUCAGACCAGGUACCGCAGCGACCCGAACCUAGCUCGGUACCCGGUGAAACCGCCGCCUGAGGAGCAGCAGAUGCGCAUGCACGCCCGGGUGUCCCGCGCCAGGCACGAGCGGCGCCACAGCGACGUGGCGCUCCCGCGCACCGAGGCGGGCGCGGCGCUGCCGGAGGGCAAGGCCGGCAAACGCGCGCCGGCGGCAGCCAGGGCCUCGCCGCCGGACUCGCCGCGGGCUUACUCGGCUGAGAGAACUGCGGAGACCAGGGCGCCGGGCGCCAAGCAGCUAACGAACCACAGCCCGCCGGCGCCCAGACAUGGGCCGGUUCCCGCAGAAGCCCCGGAGCUCAAAGCCCAGGAGCCCCUCAGGAAGCAGAGCCGCCUGGACCCCAGCUCGGCGGUCCUCAUGCGGAAGGCCAAGCGCGAGAAGGUGGAGACCAUGCUGCGGAACGACUCUUUGAGCUCAGACCAGUCCGAGUCGGUGCGGCCGUCCCCGCCCAAGCCGCACCGGUCCAAGAGAGGCGGCAAGAAGCGGCAGAUGUCGGUGAGCAGCUCUGAGGAGGAGGGCGUGUCGACGCCCGAGUACACCAGCUGCGAGGACGUGGAGCUGGAGAGCGAGAGCGUCAGCGAGAAAGGUGAUUUGGAUUAUUACUGGUUGGAUCCUGCCACGUGGCACAGCCGGGAGACAUCACCUAUUAGUUCGCAUCCUGUAACGUGGCAACCAUCUAAAGAGGGGGACCGAUUAAUUGGACGUGUUAUUCUUAACAAGAGAACAACCAUGCCCAAAGACUCAGGUGCAUUGCUGGGUCUGAAAGUUGUUGGAGGAAAAAUGACUGACUUAGGACGACUUGGUGCUUUCAUCACCAAAGUAAAGAAGGGUAGCCUAGCAGAUGUAGUUGGACACCUAAGAGCAGGGGAUGAAGUUCUAGAAUGGAAUGGUAAACCCCUGCCGGGAGCUACAAAUGAAGAAGUUUACAACAUUAUUUUAGAAUCAAAAUCAGAACCUCAAGUUGAAAUUAUUGUUUCAAGGCCUAUUGGUGACAUUCCCCGGAUUCCUGAGAGCUCCCACCCUCCACUGGAGUCCAGUUCAAGUUCCUUUGAAUCUCAGAAGAUGGAAAGGCCUUCCAUUUCUGUUAUUUCUCCAACAAGUCCUGGAGCUCUAAAAGAUGCCCCACAAGUCUUACCAGGGCAACUUUCUGUGAAGUUGUGGUAUGAUAAAGUGGGACACCAGCUGAUUGUAAAUGUUCUGCAAGCAACAGAUCUACCUGCUAGAGUAGAUGGACGUCCUCGAAAUCCCUAUGUAAAAAUGUAUUUUCUUCCAGAUAGAAGUGAUAAAAGUAAAAGGAGGACCAAAACAGUAAAGAAAAUACUAGAACCAAAAUGGAAUCAAACUUUUGUCUAUUCACAUGUACAUCGUAGAGAUUUUAGAGAACGAAUGUUAGAAAUAACUGUGUGGGACCAACCAAGAGUGCAAGAAGAAGAAAGUGAAUUUCUUGGAGAGAUCCUCAUAGAAUUGGAGACAGCGCUUUUAGAUGAUGAACCGCAUUGGUAUAAACUUCAGACACAUGAUGAGUCUUCACUACCUCUGCCUCAGCCAUCACCUUUCAUGCCAAGGCGACAUAUUCAUGGAGAAAGCUCUAGCAAAAAGCUACAAAGAUCUCAGCGAAUCAGUGAUAGUGACAUCUCAGAUUAUGAGGUUGAUGAUGGUAUUGGCGUAGUUCCUCCAGUAGGCUAUAGGUCUAGUGCUAGAGAAAGUAAAUCUACAACAUUAACUGUGCCAGAACAGCAAAGAACAACUCAUCACCGCUCACGUUCAGUAUCUCCUCAUCGCGGCAAUGAUCAGGGAAAGCCGCGUUCACGUUUACCAAAUGUGCCAUUACAGAGGAGUUUAGAUGAAAUUCAUCCAACAAGAAGGUCACGUUCUCCAACCAGACACCAUGAUGCCUCCCGAAGUCCAGUUGAUCAUAGAACCAGAGAUGUGGAUAGUCAGUAUUUAUCAGAACAAGACAGUGAGCUUCUUAUGCUGCCCAGAGCAAAACGAGGACGAAGUGCAGAAUGCCUACAUACUACCAGACAUCUUGUUAGGCACUAUAAAACAUUACCUCCCAAGAUGCCUUUAUUACAGAGCAGUUCUCACUGGAAUAUUUACAGCUCAAUUCUGCCUGCACAUACUAAGACCAAAUCAGUGACUAGACAGGACAUUUCCCUUCAUCAUGAAUGCUUUAACUCAACAGUAUUGAGAUUUACUGAUGAAAUACUGGUUAGUGAACUGCAGCCCUUUCUUGACAGGGCUAGGAGUGCUAGUACCAACUGCUUGAGACCAGAUACUAGUUUGCAUUCACCAGAACGAGAAAGGGGUAGAUGGUCCCCCUCCCUAGAUAGGAGACGACCUCCUAGUCCCAGGAUUCAAAUCCAGCAUGCGUCUCCGGAGAAUGACAGGCACUCCAGAAAGUCUGAAAGAUCUAGCAUCCAAAAACAGACUAGGAAAGGCACUGCCUCUGAUGCAGAAAGGGUUCUCCCAACAUGUCUUUCUAGAAGGGGACACGCAGCCCCAAGAGCAACUGAUCAGCCAGUCAUUAGGGGAAAACAUCCUGCUCGCUCAAGGUCGAGUGAGCACUCUAGUAUCAGAACACUGUGUUCUAUGCACCACCUUGUCCCUGGAGGGUCGGCGCCACCUUCUCCGCUUCUGACAAGAAUGCACCGACAGAGAAGUCCAACACAAUCUCCUCCAGCAGACACAUCGUUCAGCAGUCGCAGGGGAAGACAGCUCCCACAAGUGCCAGUGAGAAGCGGCAGUAUAGAACAAGCAAGCUUAGUAGUGGAGGAGCGAACAAGACAGAUGAAAAUGAAAGUGCAUCGAUUUAAGCAGACAACAGGGUCUGGUUCUAGUCAAGAACUUGAUCGCGAGCAAUAUUCCAAGUAUAACAUACAUAAAGAUCAGUACAGAAGCUGUGAUAACGUCUCUGCCAAAUCAUCAGAUAGUGAUGUCAGUGAUGUUUCCGCCAUUUCCCGAACCAGCAGUGCCUCACGCCUCAGCAGCACAAGCUUUAUGUCAGAGCAAUCUGAGCGCCCCAGGGGUAGAAUCAGUUCAUUUACCCCCAAAAUGCAAGGCAGACGGAUGGGGACUUCAGGAAGAUCCAUCAUGAAGAGCACCAGUGUCAGUGGAGAGAUGUACACACUGGAGCAUAAUGACGGCAGCCAGUCAGACACAGCUGUGGGUACAGUUGGAGCAGGUGGAAAGAAACGGAGAUCCAGCCUUAGUGCCAAAGUGGUUGCCAUAGUGUCUCGAAGGAGUAGAAGCACAUCCCAGCUUAGUCAAACAGAGUCGGGCCACAAAAAGUUAAAAAGUACCAUCCAGAGAAGCACAGAAACAGGCAUGGCAGCUGAAAUGAGAAAGAUGGUAAGGCAGCCGAGCCGAGAGUCUACUGAUGGCAGCAUCAACAGUUACAGCUCUGAGGGCAAUUUAAUAUUUCCUGGAGUGCGACUGGGAGCUGACAGUCAAUUCAGUGAUUUUCUUGAUGGAUUGGGACCAGCCCAGCUUGUUGGCCGCCAAACCCUUGCCACCCCUGCAAUGGGUGAUAUACAAAUAGGAAUGGAGGACAAAAAGGGCCAAUUAGAAGUGGAAGUCAUUAGAGCACGAAGCCUCACACAAAAGCCUGGUUCCAAAUCUACACCUGCUCCAUAUGUCAAAGUAUAUCUUUUGGAAAAUGGGGCCUGUAUAGCCAAGAAGAAGACAAGAAUUGCACGAAAAACCCUUGAUCCUUUGUAUCAGCAGUCUCUGGUUUUUGAUGAAAGUCCACAGGGUAAAGUUCUUCAGGUGAUUGUCUGGGGAGACUAUGGCAGAAUGGACCACAAAUGCUUUAUGGGUGUGGCUCAGAUCUUGUUGGAAGAACUCGACCUGUCCAGCAUGGUGAUCGGAUGGUACAAAUUGUUCCCACCGUCCUCACUGGUGGAUCCCACACUCACUCCCCUCACCCGGCGGGCUUCCCAGUCAUCUCUGGAAAGUUCAACUGGGCCUCCCUGUAUUCGAUCAUAGUGAACUCAUACCAGAGUCAUUCCAAUAAAACUCUACUUUUCAGGAUAAUAAUCUGAACCAGAUAUUUCAUGAUCGAAAGCAUUGUUGGAGACAGACAAUCAACUUGUGUUUUGCCUGUAGUAGUUUUUCAAUAAUAUGUCCCAAUUGUUAUUUAAAACAUGGCUUCAUAUGACAGAACAAGGCAAUCUAUCAAAUUUACAGGAAGAAUCAACAUGCUGGUGAGAGUCACUGAUGCUUCUAACAAAUAGAAAAAGAGGAAACUUUAAAUCCACGCAUACACGUACACACACACAUGCACACACACACACACCAAAUUGAACAAACUGGAAACUCUCACUCUGUGAAAAGUUGUAUUCUACACAUUUCUGCACAGACCACAAGCAGUGUUAUUUCCCUGAUGUUUGAGUUGUUUUGUUCUUUUGUGUGUUUUGUUUAUUUGUGUGUUGUUUGUUGGUUUUCGUUUCUUGAGUUUUUGUUUUGUUUUCACCACAUCUGUUAUUUCCACUAGUUUUUUUUUGGCUGUGUCAUGACAGGCCUCAUGAUGCUAACAGAGAUUCUUCCCUUCUUUUUUCCAAAAGCACCAAAAAAAAGGGCUGAAGUAGUCUCUGUAGCAUCUCCCCAAAGUGUUAAACAGCUACAUAAGGUGAAGCCAAGGAAGGGUUUCACUAGCUUUCAUUUUAUAAUUAUUUAAAGUCUUAUGUGUGGAUACCCAAGAGACAAAAAGUUAUCUUCCAAAAUAAAUAAUCACAGAAGUACUUUUUUAAUGAAGAGCCUAUCUGUUUGCAUUCUAGAAAAUUAAUUUAUGGUUUCCAUUGUUUUGCAUGGAAGACUUUUAAAGAAGUCAAUCUGCAACUAAUGCUGGGGACUAAAACUAACUGCAUAAUUGUACUUUGAAAACACUCCUUGUAAUGCCUUUUUCUUCCUGAUAUUAAAAAAAUGCUCAUGUGUAUAAACCAUACUUUGACUUCCCAAAAAUGGUGACUAGGAAUGGAUUUGAGCCUAAGACACUUUGAGCUAUGCCCAGGCUUCUCAGCCAUACCUCAGUGUAGACACAUCCAUCUGCCCUGGAAAGAGCAUGGUAUGAGCUGUUCAAUAUUCCACUGGAAAUUCCAGUUGAAAUAUUCUGCACUAAACUAUUGUUUUUAUUGAAUUUUAGUUUACAUUUCUUUGAGAUUGAUGCAAGCACAAAGCUUGAUUUUUUAAUGCAAAGUAUCUUACUUUUUGGGGGGAAAAUAAACAAAAUGAACUUUCAAUUUGCAUUUUCAUUUAGUUUCUCUUGGCCUUGAAUUUCCCUUGUGACAUUCUGUACAUGUGCUACAAACUGCAGUCUCUGCAGGUGCAUUGAUAUGUUCUCCCUCCUUUUAUGAGUCACUCCACUUUUGUGAUUACACAAAUAGAGCAGCAUGACUUGGAACUGUUCAGAGCUGCAUGCACAUUUUGUAAAAAAAAAAAAUUUUAAAAAGAAAAGAAACAAAAGGUUAUUUAAUAAUGUAUGUUAGUUCCACAUAGGCCAGCUUGUAUGUUGCAUGUACUUGUACAGUUUGCUUGUUAAUUACUAUACCGAAAUAACCAAGAAAUCUAAGCCAUCCACUUUUGUUAUAGACAUUUUGCAGGUUUUAGCCAGACUCAGUCUCUGGGUCUGUGGUGAAAUGUCUAUAGAUGGACUUUAUUUUUUACCCUCCGGAAAACGUGAUGUAGUACGGACCAAAUUCCUUCUAAUAAAUAUUUUGGUGUAGAUUCCUACUGUGGGGCUGUAACACAUGUAGACACUGUGUACACACUAGGUUUUAAUUCAUAGACAUACUGCCUGCACCAAGUGAAUUAUUUAUUAUUAUUUACACAUGCCAGAAUUAUCUGCCCAUCAUUCCACAGGGCACAGAUUGACCACUGCUCACCAUGCUGAGUAGGAGGAACUGAAGCAUUGGUGCACUUCUACUAGAUUCCGUUCUGUCUUAGUGGCCAACAAUCAACUGAUUAUAAUUGGGUAGUAUCUUUCUAUUUUGACCACUUGUCUUAACACUCCCCUGUGCUUUUAAAUGAAAUUCCAAUUCAUGUAUGUAAACAUGUUUAAUAAAAUUUACUUUUCAUGUCAGUCAGUAGCCAUAUGUGUUCUAUGUCUUGCCAGAUUUCCAUUGUGGGUUCUAUGGUGCAAAAUGGGAGCCAGGCCAUGGGAAGGGGAGGCUGGGGUUUGUUGUCUGCUGCGGGCAUUUGACUUGACUUGUCACUGCACUAUAUUAUGUCUUAAUCGAUGGCCCAAAGGGUACUUUGCAUCACAUACAAGUUUUCACUUCGUCAGCCUGUCUAAGUGAGCACAUGACUAUACUUCUGAAAAGUGGCAUUAUUAAAAAUAAUAAAUCUCAGUAAGAAUCAAAUGGAAGGUUGUUUUCUGCUGCUGUUUGAAUGUGCUAAUAAAAGAGACAACUCUAUUGUC